AUCCUGGGAAAUCCACCAACAUGGGGCGCAGCGGCCGCCGCCGCCGCCGCCGUCGCCGCGAGUCCCGGCCGCGGGUGCCUCCGCUUCCCUGACGCCCAGCUGGGGCCUCGCCGCCCGCCGCGGCCCGGGUCUUUGCGGCCCAGACUCGCCAGCGCGCCCUUCUCCCGCCUGCUCGCCGGGGCCAUGUGAGGGGGCAGCUCCCUCCACCGCCGCCGCCCCCUCUUCCUCCCCCGCCCCCUCUCCCUGCCCGCCCCCGUCACACGGAGCCCUGGAGGAUCCCCCGCUGCUGCCCGCCCUCCCUACGCCACCCCCACGAUGGACAGGAACUACGCGACCUCGGGCUUCACCGAGCCGCCGCCGCCGCCGCCGCCCGCGCCCCCCGCCGCCCCCGUCCCCGCCAGCGCCGCUGCGCAGCCCCCCGCCCCAGCCUGGGCGUACGAACCCCGAGCCGCCGCCGCCGCCGCCAGCAGCAGCUGCAGCAGUGGCAGCUGCAGUAGCGGCAGCAGCCCCAGCCUCAAGGCCAGUUUAAGCUAUGAAGAAGGACAUCCCUCACACUCUGAAACAGAUCUCCUUCAGAGACAGAGUUUUGCAGCCUCUCAUCAGCUUCCUGGAUAUGCUCCCACACCUCAGCCUACUGGUCUUUCUGGAAUAUUUGAUACUAGUGUGAACAGUGCCAGCAGUAACACUAAAGAGUCUUCAGUGAUGAAUUUUCUGUCUACUGCUGAAUCCCGAACUGCUCAGGCUGCUGCUUCAGGAACUACUCUCUUACCACAAUUCAGGGCUCCAUCCUGGCAGACAGGCAUGCAUUCCUCAGCAGCAACUGAGCUGUUUGCUACUGGACCUUUGCCAAGCACUGGAACACUUCCACCAUCUCUCUCUGCUUAUCAGCAUCCCACCACCUUCAGCAAUAGAAACUUUGCUACCACUUCACCUUUGGUGCUUCAGGAUUCAACUUUUAACACUACAUCAAAUGGAAUUUUAAGUCAUCAUGACCCUUUGCUACAAAUCAAGACUUCCCAGGGAACUGUUCCAACUGCUUUGGCAUUUGAGCGCCUGGGCAGUUCUGUAUUAAGUAACAGCAUACCACCUCAGUCUUCAACAUACCGCUCAGCUCAAGAGUCUGCACCCCAUCUUUUACAACCUCAAUUUAGUUUGUUGCCUUCAGCACUUGGGGGAUCCCAGCAGACUCCUCAAGCCUACAGUUCAACUCUCUUUACUAGUUCUACUGCUUCCAUUGAAAGAGCUCUUCUUCGAGAAUGUAGUGUUAUUAAACACCAUCAGCGGCCUUCAGGUACCCAGUCAAUUCAGGCACAACUGACUGGUUCACAGCACUCCUUACAUAGUUAUCUAUCAAAUUCAAGUGUAGUUAAUUUUCAGGAAACAACCAGGCAGUCAUCUUUAUCCUGUAGCCCAAUUGGAGAUUCCACUCAGGUGAGCAACGGAGGAUUACAACAGAAGACCUCCCAGGUCUCAGUGGAACUUGCUCAGUCUUACUCAUCUGCGAUUCCAUCAUCAGGGUAUCCUCCUUCUACUACAAAAAUAAAAAGCUGUUCUACAGAACAACCACUGACAUCAACCAAGACCCCUAAACCUCAAAGUAUAAUUCCUCCUGUGCAAACACUAAGCUAUUCCAAACCUUUACAUAAUCAGAGUUCUGUAAUAUCGGGCCAAGCACAAAUUUAUUCUACAGCGCAGCUACCAAGCCUUUUAUCAGUUAGUCAGUCCCAAAAUUACGGUUUAGUACAGCCACAUAAUGUGCCAUCUAUUGUUCAUUCACAGGUUUAUAGGUCCAGCAAGGUUGAGAAAUUGCCACCCUUGUAUAAAACAUUGACUUUUUCUGGGUCAUCUCAGACUGUAACUCCUGAAAAUCAGACGCUUAAUUAUUCAUCUAAUCAGCAAGAGGUAUUGUCUUCAGUUACAAAUGAGAAUUACCCUGCUCAAACAAGAGAUCUGUCUUCAGUAAGUCAGUCUCAAAGUUACUCAUCUGGUCACUCUCAGGGUUUAUCACCAGUUAGCCAGACACAGGUUAGCUAUUCAUCUCAAUCACAAGUUUUGUCAGUUGUUAGUCUUUCAGAAAGCUAUGCUUCAGGGGAGUCCCUAACAUUAACAGCCCCUUCUCUUUCUUAUUCUUCUGCCUCUCGGGCUCAGAAUUUGCCAGACUCUAGCCCGACCCAGAAUUAUAUUUCUAUGCAUUCUUCCCAAAAUGUUCAGACUCAAGAGUCAUCAUCUCCCCAGUCCCAGAAGUUUUUGCCUGCUGUCCAGUCAUCAUCUUUUGCAUCCUCUACUCAUUGUCAGACAUUACAAAAUAACAUAACUUCCCCUGACCCAAAGUCUUAUGCUGAAAGAAAGCUUGACUCAGAUGUGUAUCCAUCUUCAAAGCAAGAAGAUGGUUUUCCAAUGCAAGAGUUACAGGUGUUGCAGCCACAAGCAUCUCUUGAGUCAUCAACCCAAAGGCUAUCUGAUGGAGAAAUUAAUGCUCAAGAAUCAACUUAUAAGGUGUCAAAGGCAGAUGACAGAUAUUCUCAGAGUGUAAUCAGAAGUAAUUCCCGUCUUGAAGAUCAAGUUAUUGGGGUUGCUCUGCAAGCAUCAAAAAAAGAAGAAAGUGUUGUUGGUUCAGUGACACAACUUAACCAACAAAUUGGCCAAGUCAAUAAUGCAGCUACCCUUGAUCUUAAGAACUCAACUAAUUUAAUACAGACUCCACAAAUAAGGUUGAAUACUAAAGACUUAAAGCAGCAACAUCCUCUCAUACUUAAGGUGCAUGAGUCCAAGGUCCAGGAACAGCACGAUCAAAUAAUUAAUGCUUCAUCUCAGAUUCAAAUUCCAAAUCAUGCUUUAGGGCAUGGCCAUCAGGCAUCUCUUCCUAAUACACAGGUCCUUUUAGAUUCUGCCUGUGAUUUACAAAUUCUUCAGCAGUCAAUACUGCAGGCAGGUUUAGGUCAAGUAAAGGCAUCUUUACAAGCACAGCGUGUUCAAAGCCCUCAACAAAUAGUACAUCCCUUCCUUCAGAUGGAAGGUCAUGUUAUUCAAAGCAAUGGUGAUCAUUCUCAGCAGCAACUCCAUCCUCAAAAUUCUGAAGUUAUGAAAAUGGACCUCUCUGAGUCUUCAAAACCAUUACAACAACAUCUAACAACAAAGGGCCAUUUUAGUGAAACAAAUCAACAUGAUUCAAAGAAUCAGUUUGUUUCUCUUGGAUCGAUGUGUUUCCCAGAGGCAGUGCUUCUUAGUGAUGAAAGAAAUAUUUUAUCAAAUGUAGAUGAUAUCUUAGCAGCUACAGCAGCAGCUUGUGGAGUUACACCUACUGAUUUUUCCAAGUCAACUUCAAAUGAAACCAUGCAGGCUGUUGAAGAUGGUGAUUCUAAAUCUCAUUUUCAGCAGUCAUUAGAUGUCAGGCAUGUGACUUCAGAUUUUAACUCUAUGACAGCUACAGUAGGAAAGCCACAGAAUAUAAAUGAUACUUCCUUAAAUGGAAAUCAGGUUACUGUGAACCUUUCACCAGUACCUGCCCUUCAGUCAAAAAUGACUCUUGAUCAACAGCACAUUGAAACACCUGGUCAAAAUAUACCAACUAAAGUAACUUCAGCAGUGGUUGGACCAAGUCAUGAAGUCCAGGAGCAAAGUUCUGGCCCAUUCAAGAAACAGUCUGCUACCAAUCUUGAAUCUGAAGAAGACAGUGAAGCUCCUGUUGAUAGUACAUUAAAUAAUAACAGAAACCAAGAGUUUGUUUCUAGUAGUAGAAGUAUAAGUGGAGAGAAUGCUACAUCAGAGAGUGAAUUUACCUUAGGGGGUGACGACAGUGGUGUGUCAAUGAACCCAGCUAGGAGUGCACUUGCACUGUUGGCCAUGGCCCAAUCUGGGGAUGCAGUCAGUGUCAAGAUUGAAGAAGAAAACCAAGAUUUAAUGCAUUUUAACCUUCAAAAGAAAAGAGCUAAAGGAAAAGGGCAAGUUAAAGAGGAAGACAACAGUAAUCAGAAACAGCUGAAAAGACCUGCCCAAGGCAAACGCCAGAAUCCAAGGGGAACAGAUAUUUACUUACCGUAUACUCCUCCUUCCUCAGAAAGCUGCCAUGAUGGUUAUCAGCAUCAAGAAAAAAUGAGACAGAAGAUCAAAGAGGUGGAGGAAAAACAACCAGAAGUCAAAACAGGAUUUAUUGCUUCUUUCUUAGAUUUUCUGAAAUCCGGGCCCAAGCAGCAGUUUUCCACUCUUGCUGUACGAAUGCCUAACAGGACUAGACGGCCAGGGACCCAGAUGGUUCGUACAUUUUGUCCCCCACCACUUCCCAAGCCUUCAUCUACAACACCCACACCUUUAGUGUCUGAAACUGGCGGUAACAGUCCAUCAGAUAAAGUUGAUAAUGAACUUAAAAACUUGGAACAUUUAUCUUCAUUUUCUUCUGAUGAAGAUGAUCCUGGAUAUAGUCAAGAUGCUUAUAAAAGCGUCUCUACUCCCUUAACUACUUUGGAUGCUACUUCUGAUAAAAAGAAGAAAACAGGUAAAGUUUUACAAUUUAGAUUCAUAAUUAUUACUUUCUUCUAUUUUUCCAGCUAUAGCCCACAUUUUAAGCUUUUUUCACUUAAAGCAGGUCUGCAAGUACAUUUUCAGGACAAAAUGUAUAGAUUGCUUGAUCUGUUGAUUCCUGAGAAAGAAGCCCUACAGGUGGCAACUACUAGCCCAACUGCCAAUACUACUGGUACUGCUACUACUUCCUCAACCACUGUGGGUGCAGUUAAGCAAGAACCUCUCCACUCUACUUCAUAUGCAGUAAAUAUUCUGGAAAAUAUAAGCUCUUCAGAAUCCUCAAAGCCCAUUGAACUUGAUGGUCUUCCUUCAGACCAGUUUGCAAAAGGACAGGACACUGUUGCCAUAGAAGGUUUUACAGAUGAGGAGGACACAGAAAGCGGAGGAGAAGGCCAAUACAGAGAGCGUGAUGAAUUUGUGGUAAAGAUAGAAGACAUAGAGACUUUUAAGGAGGCUUUAAAAACAGGAAAAGAACCUCCAGCUAUUUGGAAAGUACAAAAAGCUUUAUUACAGAAAUUUGUUCCUGAAAUUCGAGAUGGUCAAAGAGAAUUUGCUGCUACAAAUAGUUAUCUUGGAUAUUUUGGAGAUGCAAAGAGUAAAUACAAAAGAAUAUAUGUGAAGUUCAUUGAAAAUGCAAACAAGAAGGAAUAUGUCAGAGUGUGUUCUAAAAAGCCAAGAAAUAAACCUUCACAAACUAUCAGAACUGUUCAAGCUAAGCCAAGUAGUAGCAGUAAAACUUCUGAUCCUCUAGCAUCAAAAACUACAACUACAAAAGCCCCUUCCGUGAAACCCAAAGUUAAACAGCCAAAAGUAAAGGCUGAGCCACCACCAAAGAAACGGAAAAAAUGGAAAGAAGAAUUUUCAUCAUCCCAAUCUGACUCAUCUCCUGAGAUCCAUACUAGUAGUAGUGACGAUGAGGAAUUUGAACCUCCCGCUCCCUUUGUCACUCGCUUUUUGAACACAAGAGCAAUGAAGGAAACCUUUAAGAGCUACAUGGAAUUGCUUGUUAGCAUUGCCUUGGACCCUGACACAAUGCAAGCCUUAGAGAAGAGCAAUGAUGAGCUACUUUUACCUCAUAUGAAAAAAAUAGAUGGCAUGCUAAAUGAUAACCGAAAGAGACUUCUUUUGAAUCUUCAUUUGGAUCAAUCAUUCAAGAAUGCUUUGGAAAGUUUUCCUGAACUAACAAUAAUUACUCGAGAUUCUAAAGCAAAGAGUGGAGGAACUGCUAUUUCUAAAAUCAAAAUGAAUGGCAAAGCCUAUAAUAAGAAAACUCUAAGGACUUCUAAAACAACCACCAAAUCUGCACAAGAGUUUGCUGUCGAUCCAGAGAAAAUACAGUUGUAUUCUUUGUAUCAUUCACUCCAUCAUUAUAAGUACCAUGUUUAUCUGAUAUGUAAGGAUGAGAUUUCUUCGGUGCAGAAAAAAAAUGAAGAUUUAGGACAGGAGGAAAUUGUUCAACUUUGUAUGAAAAAUGUAAAAUGGGUGGAGGACCUCUUUGAAAAAUUUGGAGAACUUCUAAAUCAUGUACAGCAGAAAUGUUCCUGACUUUUCCACAAAAAUCCCAUCUUUUUAUAGCACUAAUGAAAUGGCAGAUAUGGGGUGGUCAAAGAUAAUCAGAUGUCAAGUAGUGGCCUUCUGCAGGCCGGCCGCUUCCAUCAUGGAACUGUCAUUACCACCUCUGCUGAAGGACAGUGGUGCGGCCUUUAGGAACGAAGUUAGUCCUCUGGAAAUGGACCUAAAUCCCACCACAUUUUUACCCUAAUGAAUGAUUUUUCUAUUUUGUAAACCAUUGGGUAACUUGAGUCAUAUUUUCAGAAACAUUUUUUGACAAAUGAUGAAGCAUGCACUAAGUAUAAUUUUUUUUUAUUGCUAGAGAAGUAACACUUAAAGUAACGAUUUUUUUUUUCUGACUCCGGCUAAACACCAGAAUGACAGAGAAGUGGCAGAAACCAUAUGUUUGUACUCACAUCUGGCCACAAAACCAGAAAUACUGUACAUUAUGUAAAGAGGUCUGGUGUGGUGUGACAUCCUGUAUAAGAAUAUCAUCAAUUUAAAAUAUAAAAUUUGGAAACUAUUCUGCUUUACAGACUCCUUUUACUCUUAACAUGUUCAGGAAACUGGAUGUGGAAUUGGUGCAAUUCUCUGACUGCUUUUUGUGUCAAAUUAUAUUGUGAUAAAAAAACAAUGACAUACUAUUUUCCCUAUCGCAAAGAAAAGUAUUUUCGUUUAUACUGUUUUUUCCUUUGGAAAAUUUUCAAUUGUACAUUUUAUUUCACUGAUAGUUGUAUUUUUCACAAGGAAAAUGUUGUGGUUAUAAUUACGUUUGAUAUAUCUCUACAACACCUUUUGUUAUUUUCAGUAAAUCUUAGUUAUAUGUUGAAUUUCUAAUGUGAAUUCUAUCUUGAGGUAACCAUUUUUUUCAUACAGAUUUGCUUCAGUGUUAUCCAGAAUAUGCAUUCAGUACUAGAAUUAGUUUAGCUUUAUAAAUAGGGCUGUGUUAGACACUGCAGUAAUUUUCUAAUUCAUAAAAUAAACUUCUUACUAAACUAGCACUUGAUUAACUUGUUGAGGUAAAAAUCUAACUACAUUUACAUUUUGAAGAAUAAAACUGAUAAUUAGACUAUUUGCAGUGUUAAACACAGCUUCCUUAACUCUUAGAACUGGAAGUUGUAGAGCUCUCCUUUUGGUGCCUUUCCAGCCUUUAUACACACUAUUGUAGCUUUCUUAGGUUUGAUAGGUAGCGUUUCAAGUAGUUUAGCUGAGACAGUGAAUGUAUUAGGUUCAACAUGACCUUGUGUUUUAUUUGUGUUUGCCAACAGGAUGCCUUAUUUGUUUGAGAAAAAGAUGUACUAGUGUCAUUCUAAACUAUCUCCUUUUUUAGGAUUCUAAAGAAGUUAAUCAUCAUCCUUUUGUUUAUUUUACCACCAUUUAGUGCCUUAAAUCCUAUCAAGAAAGCAGUGUUACUGCUCAAUGCCCAAAUAAGACACGCGGAUAUUGCUAUUGUCUUGCUUUUGAGUUAACAGGCCAACUUUUUAUACUUAAAACCUCAGUAAACUGGCAAAGAAUUGAAGGUAAUGUGAUUUGAUUUGAGAAUAAAACAUUGUAGCAUUGGGUGAAAAAUGAGUAUUUGAGUUAAGCUUACAUAUUUAUUUCUGAUGGUUAUCUUAUUAAAAGCAAUAAUCCUUAAUACUGUACUUGCCAUUAGACUAGGUACUCAGUAAUGGAAGUUUCUCUCAAGGGUUAAAUGUUCCAUUUUUGAAAGUUUUAAAAAACCUGUUUGGGUGGUUUAUUUUGAAAACAAAAGUAACCUAUUAGAUUCAUUUUGCCUAACUCAUAUGAGAGAUGCAGAGUAUCAACAGUGGGAGCAUCAUAAAAUGAAUUUUCCAAGUGGAGAGGAGUAGGAAGCAGCCAUAUGAUAGUAUUGACUCUGGACAGAAUUGAUGUCUUUCGUUUCCAAAGUGCAGAGUAGGGAACUACAUUUCCUAAUGUGGCAUUGUAAAUAUACAUCUUUAUAUUACUCUUCCAGCCUACGUUCCUAAAUCAUUGAUAAUUUAAAUAUUUUUUAAAGCCACCUUAAUUUAGGUAGCUCUUGGAAUCGAUGUUUGAAUUCACUAGCCACAUUUUCUUCAUGAUAUGCCUCGUGGCAAACAAAGAUGUUUCCUUAAGAUGAAUCUUACAUUUCCCAUAGAAAAUAACCCAUUUCCUUUGGCACUGCAGUUGCCCUCAAACUGCUUGCAGUUGUAUUCAUUUUAGUACAACAAAGGUUUUCAUAAUAUGGGAGGCCAAGUCUAUGAUACUGCCUCAAAGAGACCCUAUUGUGUAGAUGCAUCAUCUUCUCUCAUUUGAUCCAUAGAGCAUAGGCAAAGAUGUCAACCUCAGGCCUUAGAGAAAAGUGGAAAUGUUAUUAUGACAGCCGUCCAUGAGUUAUCGCUUUGUAUGAAGUUAAAUACAGUCAUGCGUUGCUUAACAGCAGGGAUACAUUCUGAGAAAUGCAUUGUUAGGCAAUUCCGUUGUGCGAACAUCCUAGUGUACUUACACAAACCUAGGUGGCAUAGCCCACAACGUACCCAGGCUAUAUGGUAAACCUGUACAGCAUGUUACUGUACUGAAUACUGUAGGCAGUUGUAACACAAUGGUAUUUGUGUAUCUAGACAUAGAAAACAUACAGUAAGAAUAUGGUAUUAUAAUCUUACGGGACCACUGUCAAAUACGCGGUCUGUCUUUGAAAAGUUGUAAUGCGGCGCAUGACUAUAAAUACCUAGCUGGUUAGCAUUUACAUUCCUUGCCAGGGAGUUUGAAAUUUAUACUAUAGAAAUAACUUUAGGUUUUAGGUAGAGUUAAAGAGGUAAAGCACAUGUUGCCACAACCCAGGAAAGUAUUUUUAAGAAAGAUUGGAUUUUCCUACCUUUAGAGAUCUAAAAAAAAUUUAAUAUAAAAAAUCAUUUUGUGUUGGUGUUUAUUACUAGUUCAGAUGAGUGGCUGCUGAAGGGGCCCCCUUGUCAUUUUCAUUAUAACCCAAUUUCCACUUAUUUGAACUCUUAAGUCAUAAAUGUAUAAUGACUUAUGAAUUAGCACAGUUAAGUUGACACUAGAAACUGCCCAUUUCUGUAUUACACUAUCAAAUAGGAAACAUUGGAAAGAUGGGGAAAAAAAUCUUAUUUUAAAAUGGCUUAGAAAGUUUUCAGAUUACUUUGAAAAUUCUAAACUUCUUUCUGUUUCCAAAACUUGAAAAUAUGUAGAUGGACUCAUGCAUUAAGACUGUUUUCAAAGCUUUCCUCACAUUUUUAAAGUGUGAUUUUCCUUUUAAUAUACAUAUUUAUUUUCUUUAAAGCAGCUAUAUCCCAACCCAUGACUUUGGAGAUAUACCUAUAAAACCAAUAUAACAGCAGGGUUAUUGAAGCAGCUUUCUCAAAUGUUGCUUCAGAUGUGCAAGUUGCAAAUUUUAUUGUAUUUGUAGAAUACAAUUUUUGUUUUAAACUGUAUUUCAAUCUAUUUCUCCAAGAUGCUUUUCAUAUAGAGUGAAAUAUCCCAGGAUAACUGCUUCUGUGUCAGUCGCAUUUGACGCAUAACUGCACAAAUGAACAGUGUAUACUCUUGGUUGUGCAUUAACUUACAUGUAUAAUUUUUGGCAUCUGUGUUCACAAAUGCAUGUGUUAGCAAAUCACCUUUAUUUAUAAGUGACAAUAAUUGAAGUUAAGGAUAUAAAGAAACCUGCAUUUGUAGUCCAGCGUUUUCAUUUGGUCCAUAACACAAUGUAUGGAAAUGUGAAAGACAAUUUUGUACAUUUGUUUGUUACUAACUCAGAUCAUUAAAAUGAAAACAAUUUUUUUAAACAAGAAAA